AUUCUGUAAGUCAUAGAAAAGUUUGAAACAUUCUGUCUGUGGUAGAGCUCGGGCCAGCUGUAGUUCAUUCGCCAGUGUGCUUUUCUUAAUAUCUAAGUCUUAUUUUCAGAAACUAUGAAUAAAUCUUCUACACCAUCUUCCCGAGAGCUUUAGUAAGACCUCAGACUGGAGUAGAGUUGAAGGAGGGAAUGCCAGUCUGAAGAAGGAAAGGAAGAGGAGAGACAGCAAGGAGAACUUCAGUUGUCAAGAUGGUGCGUGAGCAGUACACUACAGCCACAGAAGGCAUCUGCAUAGAGAGGCCAGAGAAUCAGUAUGUCUACAAAAUUGGCAUUUAUGGCUGGAGAAAGCGCUGUCUCUACUUGUUUGUUCUUCUUUUACUCAUCAUCCUCGUUGUGAAUUUAGCUCUUACAAUUUGGAUUCUUAAAGUGAUGUGGUUUUCUCCAGCAGGAAUGGGCCACUUGUGUGUAACAAAAGAUGGACUGCGCUUGGAAGGGGAAUCAGAAUUUUUAUUCCCAUUGUAUGCCAAAGAAAUACACUCCAGAGUGGACUCAUCUCUGCUUCUACAAUCAACCCAGAAUGUGACUGUAAAUGCGCGCAACUCAGAAGGGGAGGUCACAGGCAGGUUAAAAGUCGGUCCCAAAAUGGUAGAAGUCCAGAAUCAACAGUUUCAGAUCAACUCCAACGACGGCAAGCCACUAUUUACUGUAGAUGAGAAGGAAGUUGUGGUUGGUACAGAUAAACUUCGAGUAACUGGGCCUGAAGGGGCUCUUUUUGAACAUUCAGUGGAGACACCCCUUGUCAGAGCCGACCCGUUUCAAGACCUUAGAUUAGAAUCCCCCACUCGGAGUCUAAGCAUGGAUGCCCCAAGGGGUGUGCAUAUUCAAGCUCACGCUGGGAAAAUUGAGGCGCUUUCUCAAAUGGAUAUUCUUUUUCAUAGUAGUGAUGGAAUGCUUGUGCUUGAUGCUGAAACUGUGUGCUUACCCAAGCUGGUGCAGGGGACGUGGGGUCCCUCUGGCAGCUCACAGAGCCUCUACGAAAUCUGUGUGUGUCCAGAUGGGAAGCUGUACCUGUCUGUGGCCGGUGUGAGCACCACGUGCCAGGAGCACAACCACAUCUGCCUCUGAGCUGCCUGCGUCCUCUCGGUGAGCUGUGCAGUGCCGGCCCCAGAUCCUCACACCCAGGGAGCAGCUGCACAUCGUGAAAGACUGAGGCAGCGUGGAUGGGAAGUAAACGCUUCCAGAGGAACUCAGAAAAAAUUAUGUGCCAGUGAAAGUGUUUGGACAAAAACUACAUGAUCUCAAAAUGCACGUGGAUGUGAGACACAAAAGUUGACAAAAUGGAAAAGCAAUGUGUUUUUCCACUGGAUUAAUUUUCACCGGAACAAUUGCGAAUUCUCUCUGCCUCGCCUCCCCCUAUCUUGUCCGUGUGGGCACACACUGAGUGUUGAGUUGCCGUGUGGAGUUAAUGUAUGACGCUCCACUGUGGAUAUCUAAUGCCCUGUUGAGAGUAGCCUUGCUCAGUACUAAAAUGCCCCAAAGUUCUAUACAGCAUUUCCUUUAUAGCAUUCAAACCUCACAUCCUCCCUUCAGUUUAAUGCAAGUAAGUCAGGUUUCACAAGAAAAUUUUCAAGUUUUGAAGGGAAUUUGAGGUUGAUCUGGUUUUCAAGAUGUAGUUAAAGGAAUAAAUCACUCAAAAUUAAACUUUCUGUAUAUAGUCAAUAAGCAAUAAAAACCUCAUUUUUCAGA